AGUCCCUGACGUGUCGGGGAGGAGCCGGGCGCGGAGGUACGCUGAGUGGAGCUCGGGGCUGCGUAGGGGAGCUGAGCCGAGCGGCUGGGCGGGCCUGGCCGGGCCGGCGGAGGGGAGACGUCGGUUGAGCGGCGGCGAACAUGCGCUUUUGACACAUUGGAGAAGACCACGUGGCCUUAAACCAACUGCUGCAACUCUGUGUGCAGGAUGAUUCUGUGGGCCCAAGUCACCCAGCGCCUAUGCUGCAACCAAAAGUGCCUCCUGUCGCUUUGUAUCAAAGGACCUUUGUCAUGAUCUCAUUCACAAUAUUGGUGGUCCCUGAGAGUGGAGCAGUGGAGUGAUUGACGUGCCUGAGUUUGAAGAGAGUUAACCACUGGAAUCUCUCAUGUUUUAUUCCCUCCAAAAUGCUGCAGCUUUCUUGAUCAUGGAUGGUGAAGAUAUACCAGAUUUUUCAAGUUUAAAGGAGGAAACUGCUUAUUGGAAGGAACUUUCCUUGAAGUAUAAGCAAAGCUUCCAGGAAGCUCGGGAUGAGCUAGUUGAAUUCCAGGAAGGAAGCAGAGAAUUAGAAGCAGAGUUGGAGGCACAAUUAGUACAGGCUGAACAAAGAAAUAGAGACUUGCAGGCUGAUAACCAAAGACUGAAAUAUGAAGUGGAGGCAUUAAAGGAGAAGCUAGAGCAUCAAUAUGCACAGAGCUAUAAGCAGGUCUCAGUGUUAGAAGAUGAUUUAAGUCAGACUCGGGCCAUUAAGGAGCAGUUGCAUAAGUAUGUGAGAGAGCUGGAGCAGGCCAACGACGACCUGGAGCGAGCCAAAAGGGCAACAAUAGUUUCACUGGAAGACUUUGAACAAAGGCUAAACCAGGCCAUUGAACGAAAUGCAUUUUUAGAAAGUGAACUUGAUGAAAAGGAAUCUUUGUUGGUCUCUGUACAGAGGUUAAAGGAUGAAGCAAGAGAUUUAAGGCAAGAACUAGCAGUUCGGGAAAGACAACAGGAAGUAACUAGAAAGUCGGCUCCUAGCUCUCCAACUCUAGACUGUGAAAAGAUGGACUCCGCCGUCCAAGCAUCACUUUCUUUGCCAGCUACCCCUGUUGGCAAAGGAACGGAGAACACUUUUCCUUCACCGAAAGCUAUACCAAAUGGUUUUGGUACCAGUCCACUAACUCCCUCUGCUAGGAUAUCAGCACUAAACAUCGUGGGGGAUCUCUUACGGAAAGUAGGGGCUUUAGAAUCCAAAUUAGCAGCUUGCAGGAAUUUUGCAAAGGACCAAGCAUCACGAAAAUCCUAUAUUUCAGGGAAUGUUAACUGUGGGGUGCUGAAUGGCAAUGGCACAAAGUUCUCUCGAUCAGGGCAUACAUCUUUCUUCGACAAAGGGAGUCGGGCAAUGACACCAUCACAGCUGCGCCUACUGACAGUGAUUGUGAGAUACAGGAGAUGUGGCCCACGUGAAGCUGGGGGUGCCUUGGCACCUGUGCAGUAUGGCACAUACUUGGGAGAGGCAGCGCUCUGCAUGGGGAUCUGUGAGACCCAGUUUGUCGGUUAUGUCACGUUACCUCUCGAAUAAGGCUUUGUGACAUCCAGUCAGCCGGAAUGGAGCCUGUUACUGGGCUGCUUAGUCUCAGUAGGGGUUGAAGUCCGGGGCCACACUUUCUGCCCAGCUUACAGGCUCUGUAGCUAUAGUGAAUGCCUUUGAAAAGCAGUAGCAUGAUGGACUUACACCCUUUCAAUAGCUUCAUAUAAGAUUCCCAACAAGAAUGAGGUACUUCACAAUCUGCUUGAUUCCCAAAUGGCAGGUGCCUACAGAAGGAAGUGGACUUCUCUGUCUGGUCCUGACAGCUGACUUAGGACGGCAUUUUGGCAAAAACUCAACAUCUGGGAAAGCUCUUGGUGCAGAUGUUGUCCCCGAAAGGUGGAAAGGGAGAGGUCCUUUCUUGCAUUCCUCCCAGAGACUGGGAAGCCUGUGUGGGUGGGGCCUCGCAAGGGGAGACCUGCCUGGAACUCAAGGGAGAGGAGUCCUCACCACUUCCUAACGAUUCCAACCUGGAGCCUGUUCUGGCUUUUUUCUUUUUUUGGGAGUGAAGGAAGAGCAGGAAGGUGUGGUUUGACAACAGUGAGCUCUCUUCUCCAGUCUUGAUGUGGACAUGUCUGUCCCUCAGCAGCACCGGCCUCUGGGGAGAAGGGCCCUGGGUCGGUCAUACCCAGAGCCAUAGAAAGGGCUGGCUAGAACAGCUUGGCCUUACGGCUCACAGUUCAUCUUAGCUGAGGUUUCCUGGGACAGGAAAAAUUGGUGACACAAAGAUGUGACAAAUCUAUAGCCUGAUGCCAUCAGGAAUUGGAAGUGUCCCCUCAAGCCAGCAGGCUAGAAAUAGGUGUUAGCUGGGCAUGGUGGCUCACACCUGUAAUCCCAGCACUUUGGGAGGGAGGCCAAGGCGGGACGAAUCACGUGAGGCCGGGAGUUCAAAACCAACCUGUCCAACAUGGUGAAACCCCGUUUCUACAAAAAAAGAAAAUACAAAAAUUAGCCAGGCCUGGUGGCGGGCGCCUGUAAUCCCAGCUACUCGGGGGGCUGAAGCAGAGAAUGGCUUGAACCCGGAGGUGGAGGGUGAAGUGAGCUGAGAGCAUGCCACUGCGCUCCAGCCUGGGAGACAGAGCGCGACUCUGUCUCGGGAAAAAAAACAAGUUGUUAUCCUUCCAAAGCAGUUUAAAAAUAGUCCACUGGAAUGGCUGCAUUAAAGAAAAUAAAUAAAAACAACAACAAAAACUGGCAUCUAUGAUGUGGCAAGGGCAGAGCGCUUAUGGCCCUAAACGAAGCCCCGGCACUGCCUCAUGUCGUCUAGACCCAGGCUCAACGAAAGAGCAAGCCUUUCCCAAGUCUUGCCUGAGUUCCUCCUCACCGGGAACCACACUGCUGCUGGGUAGAAGCUGACCAGCUUGAUCUUCUGAUACACUCAAAGCCCAGCUGCCAUAAACUGUCUUCCUUGUGCUCUGAAUGCCCAACGAAGGUUGUAUAAACUACCUUUCCUUAGGUCUGGAGUGUCGGGUCAGUCAAGAAGGGACCCUUUUAGUUAUUAAAUAGUAUCUUUGCAGAAUCAGGGCCUGGAAUUGGUUCACACAGAUUGUUUCUCCUGGCACGCUGAGUAGUUGGGAAACUGUGACGUGAACACCAGUUAGAUCAGCCAGUAGGGAAGAAUUCUUUUUUUUUUUGAGACGGAGUCGCCCUUCUCUGUCACCCAGGCUGGAGUGCAGUGGUGUGAUCUCGGCUCACUGCAGCCUCCACCUCCCAGGUUCAAGUGAUUUUCAUGCCUCAGCCCCCCAAGUAGCUGGGACUACAGGUGUGCACCACCACACCUGGCUAAUUUUUGUAUUUUUAGUAGAGACGGUGUUUCACCAUGUUGGCCAGGCUGGAUUCGAACUUCUGACCUCAAAUGAUCCACCUGCUUUGGCCUCCCAAAGUGCCGGGAUUACAGGCGUGAGCACCAUGCCCAGCCCAGAGUUCUUACUUUUUGAGAAAAACAAGCCUCUGAAUUCUGUACACUCUUGGAUAAGAUACUGGAUGUGGGGGUGGGAGCCCUGCUGAAGCACCAUACCUGUGACUCACCUUUCCUCUCCUAUGGUAGUGGCACAGGAGGAAGAGGGCACUUCGGCCCAUUUCACACGUUUCUACUGCUGCCAAGAAGCCUAGUCAUAGACCCCUUACCCCCAGAACCAGUCUAACCGGAGAAUAUUAUGGAACAAGAAAUCGGCAUUCUCUGUUUGAUUCUGUGCUGCCCUAGUAUUUCUCUCAUCCUAGUUGGCCCGCACUAGAGAGGCUGCCCUUGGCCUCAUCACUGAAUCCUCCAAAAGCAUCUUCAAUGCGUGUCUGCCUGAAAAUGCAGCCUGAAAUGUCCUGGACCCCUGAAAAUGUCCUAACCCAGCAGUGAGCUUCAUUGGCUGGUGACCAGAGCCCUCCUAAAUCACUCCCUUGACAGGUGGGCCAGCUCCUGCCUUUGGGUGGUCUUUCCCUUCCUAGUGCGUGUGCAUCCUGUGAGGCACUGGCAGGAACAAGAGUUGGAGCCAGGACUGGCCUGAGAAUUAUUCUGUCGUCUGACCUGGGAGACAGCGCCCUCAGCAAAAAGGGCCUGGCGCCAUCAUUUGAAGUUGGUGUGUAGCACCCACCCUCCAGUCAGAUCACAGAUGGGAAAUCGAGAACAGAAGGUGAGAAAACAGAUUCCACGUUCACAUGAUUAUUCUUGUUUAUUGAGGUCUCUUUAUUCUCCACGGGUGCUUUUUUCUUCAAGUAAACAGAGCAGGCGCAAAUAUCUAUAAUGAAUAAAUUUAUUGUCUUACAAAAA